GAAUUUGCUGCUACUUAACGCUGUAUUAUAGGCACAUGCUUUUUCAGCUGGGCCAAAAUGUAGAGGAGAUAGAAAUAAAUCUAAUUAAUAGAAGUAUACUUGUUAAAGGAGCUUUCAGAAUGACAACUUUCUCUUGCCUGGGGUAAGAUGCAGGCAAAGAGAAUGGUCUGAUAGAGCACCAUGAUGUGCUUCAAAGGUUCCUACAAGUUUAGAACUCAGGGUUGGCCAUGCAUUGUAGAAUUAGAAGUUUAGGCAUAUAUUCAAUCAACUAUUCAGUCUUCCUUCGGGAAGGCAUUCAAAAGGCACUAGUGUCUCUUCCUCACUCCCACCCAGCCCAGAGGUAGCCAUUGUCACCAAUUUAUUGAUGUAUUCGCCUUUUUGAUUAUCUCAGGAGUAGGUGCCAGUUUUCUCUCUAAGCCAUUUUACUUCUGCCAGUUCUGAAUAUUCAGUCUGGGACUUAUCACUGUUUCCUGUUGCCUGCCGCAGCAUUUUUCAUCGUAGAUAGUAGUAAUGUUUUGAAAUCUAUCUAGCAAUCAUAAGAGUCUUAAAAUUCUUAACCUUGAAUGUGGAAUUUUAAAAAGUUACAUACUUUUUAACAAUUUAGGGGAAAGUAUGAAAGUUUUAAGAACAUAGUAGCUUGAAUAAUUGAAAUAGAAAAUCUCUCAGUGACGUAAGUGGACAUUUUGAGAAUGCAAACUGUUUUAUUACAUUGCAUAUAAAUGAUAUUUUGCACAUUUUUUUUUAUAAAGAGAGAGUAAAAUGCACGUAUCAUUUGUCAGUCCAAAGGUAAUGUCCCCCUUUUUGCCAAAUACUAUACAAUUAGACAAAACUCUGUAGGAUUUCUCUGAAUAAAAGGGUUGAUUUUGUUUUUUAAAUAGAGUAUAUGAUAAAAGCGAUAAAGUACCUAUGCAAGAAUUAAUGGUAUAGUGUAGGCUAAACUCUUCUUCAUAUUGAUCCUAAUACAGGUAAUUAUGUUAUCUUUCCUAAUUAUAGCUUAUUUUGUUAUAGCUAUCACAUUGUUUUGUAACAUACAAAAAAGUAUAAUUAUACAAAGACUCCACUUUACAAAUGUAAAUACAGUCUUGGUUUGGUGUAUAUUGGAUACAAUGGUCUUCCUUAAGCCUAAACACAGAAACAAAAGCAUAUUAUAAGAGAAAGUCCAAGAUGGGAAGUGAUAAAGUGGGUAUUGAGUAGAGCUUUGUUAAAAUUUAGCUGGUAUCCUUGUAAAAUUUCCAUGUAUUCAUUAAAUUAUAUUAUGUCAUUCUUAUUUUUAGGAGCUGACUUGAAGUUUUAAGUUUUGCCCUCAUAAAGAAUUGUCACAAUUUGGUUAUUACAGUUGGAUGAUUCUGAUUUUUUAAAAAUUCUUUUUGUAUAUAUUUGUAUAGGUAUUAAAAUUGAAAUUGUUCAAUGACUAAAGUUAAGGCUUUAAACGUAUUGGGGCAUAUUUUAUUUCAACAGCAAAAAGUAGAACUGAUUUUGAACUGGACAAGGUUAUCUUCUCAGUUACUGUAAAUUUUACAAGUUUGAGAAUAAAAUAAUAUUUAGAAUGCUAGCUGUGCUGUUUAUAUUUCAAGAUCAUUAAAGCACUCUUGGCUUGUGUGGUCUUUAAAGAUGGGUUUAUCAAAUAUUUAUUUAACAUUGGUAGGUAUGUGUAAUUCUCAGAAAAAAAAUCUAGGACUGCAAAACAAAGCGGGAUAAUUCCUUCUCUCAUUCAACAAUACAAGGUGUCACAGAAAUCUCAGUGAAGUUUUAAUUUUUAAAACUCCAGAAUUAUAUAUGUUAUAAACUUAAACACCAUUGAGAAAUUCAGUUACUGGAAUUUCUUUUAUACUUAUUUAUUUUUGUGAGUUUUUUUUUCUUUUUUGAGACAGAGUCUCACUCUGUUCCCAGGCCGGAGUGCAGUGGUGUGAUCUCUGCUCAUUGCAACCCUCCGCCUCCUGGGUUCAAGCAAUUCUCCUGCCUCAGCCUCUCCCUAGUAACUAGGAUUACAGAUAUGCACCACCACACCUGCCUAAUUUUUGUAUUUUUAGUAGAGAUGGGGUUUCACUAUGUUGGCUGGACUGGUCUCAAACUCCUGGCCUCAUGUGAUCCUCCUGCCUUGGCCUCUCAAAGUGCUGGGAUUAUAGGCGUGAGCCACUGCACCCAGCUGUGAAUUUUGAAUGAUGCGCUUUUUUUUUUUUGGUGUGUGUGUGUGAUGGAGUCUUGCUCUGUCAUGCUGGCUGGAGUGCAGUGGCGCAGUCUUGGCUUACUGCAACCUCCACCUCCAGGUUCAAACGAUUCUCCUGCCUCAGCCUCCUAAGUAGCCAGGAUUACAGGCGCAUGCUACCUUGCCUGGCUCAUUUUUGUAUUUUUAGUAGAGAUGGGGUUUCACCAUGCUGACCACGCUGGUCUCAAACUCCUGACCUCAGGCAUUCCACCCGCCUCGGUGAAUAAUGCAUUUUUAAUUUUAGUUUUUUACUUCAGUACUGCUGAAGAUGGCAAAUACUGACUGAAGGAAAAAAUUAAAUUAAAAAUGUAUUAUUCAAAAUUGCUUUGCCUGAACUUUUACUUGAUUACAGGUCGUUAUUUAAAUCACUUCGUGAAAUUACCUACUUUGGAAUUGUAGGCACGUACAUAGACUAUCCUUAAAAAAAUUCAACACUCUCCACACUCACUAUUAUAAUAUUGUUACAACUCUUGAGAAACUCAGGUUUGAAGCAAAGAUGUCUUUGAGGUUUGGAGAUUUCUGUGUCUGAAAACAACUGAUCUUGUUUUAAGGAAUGAAAUCUGACUAACUUUUAGCAUGGUAUAGGAUAAAUAGUAUACUUUAAUUGUUUGUAGUAAUUACAUAAUGUGAAAAAAUAAGUAAACUUUCAAAAAUUGGCAUAUUUAAUGUAGUGAGAUUUUUUUUCCCAGUAGCUUCACUUUGUCCCAUACUGUUUUUUUUUUUUUUUUUUUAAACUCACACAGCAAAUCAAGUUUAUUAUAAAUUCAAGGAAGGGUUUGGUUAAGCACAAUAGCCUAUAAGCUCCUUGCUAUUUAGAUAACAUCAAGACUCAGGCAUGCACUGUGGAAUUGGAACUUCGGUGAGCUAACUAGCUAGGAUUUAUUCAAAUAAUAGGAGCUCUACGAGUGACAGAUGGCAGAAGGGCACAUCUUCUGAAAACUUACUAAAAAUUGGUGAAUUACAAAAUUCUAAAUUUUAAUACCUUAAUCAUUUUGAAAGCAGUUCAGACAGAACCGAAACAGAAAUAUUUGGCAUAAAAUUCCAAAUUUUUAUGCUUAGUUUUAUUUUUAUUAUUAAAAGCCAGCUUUUGAAAGCUGUGCAAAUAUCAGGAAUUGGGAAGAAUGAUGAUAUAGUGCUACUGUGAUCUUCCAUUGUUUGAAGCACUGGACCUUUAAUCCACUGUAGGUAUGGACAGGGAAGAAAGGAAGACCAUCAAUCAGGGUCAAGAAGAUGAAAUGGAGAUUUAUGGUUACAAUUUGAGUCGCUGGAAGCUUGCCAUAGUUUCUUUAGGAGUGAUUUGCUCUGGUGGGUUUCUCCUCCUCCUCCUCUAUUGGAUGCCUGAGUGGCGGGUGAAAGCGACCUGUGUCAGAGCUGCAAUUAAAGACUGUGAAGUAGUGCUGCUGAGGACUACUGAUGAAUUCAAAAUGUGGUUUUGUGCAAAAAUUCGCGUUCUUUCUUUGGAAACUUACCCAGUUUCAAGUCCAAAAUCUAUGUCUAAUAAGCUUUCAAAUGGCCAUGCAGUUUGUUUAAUUGAGAAUCCCACUGAAGAAAAUAGGCACAGGAUCAGUAAAUAUUCACAGACUGAAUCACAACAGAUUCGUUAUUUCACCCACCAUAGUGUAAAAUAUUUCUGGAAUGAUACCAUUCACAAUUUUGAUUUCUUAAAGGGACUGGAUGAAGGUGUUUCUUGUACGUCAAUUUAUGAAAAGCAUAGUGCAGGACUGACAAAGGGGAUGCAUGCCUACAGAAAACUGCUUUAUGGAGUAAAUGAAAUUGCUGUAAAAGUGCCUUCUGUUUUUAAGCUUCUAAUUAAAGAGGUUCUCAACCCAUUUUACAUUUUCCAGCUGUUCAGUGUUAUACUGUGGAGCACUGAUGAAUACUAUUACUAUGCUCUAGCUAUUGUGGUUAUGUCCAUAGUAUCAAUCGUAAGCUCACUAUAUUCCAUUAGAAAGCAAUAUGUUAUGUUGCAUGACAUGGUGGCAACUCAUAGUACCGUAAGAGUUUCAGUUUGUAGAGUAAAUGAAGAAAUAGAAGAAAUCUUUUCUACCGACCUUGUGCCAGGAGAUGUCAUGGUCAUUCCAUUAAAUGGGACAAUAAUGCCUUGUGAUGCUGUGCUUAUUAAUGGUACCUGCAUUGUAAACGAAAGCAUGUUAACAGGAGAAAGUGUUCCAGUGACAAAGACUAAUUUGCCAAAUCCUUCAGUGGAUGUGAAAGGAAUAGGAGAUGAAUUAUAUAAUCCAGAAACACAUAAACGACAUACUUUGUUUUGUGGGACAACUGUUAUUCAGACUCGUUUCUACACUGGAGAACUCGUCAAAGCCAUAGUUGUUAGAACAGGAUUUAGUACUUCCAAAGGACAGCUUGUUCGUUCCAUAUUGUAUCCCAAACCAACUGAUUUUAAACUCUACAGAGAUGCCUACUUGUUUCUACUAUGUCUUGUGGCAGUUGCUGGCAUUGGGUUUAUCUACACUAUUAUUAAUAGCAUUUUAAAUGAGGUACAAGUUGGGGUCAUAAUUAUCGAGUCUCUUGAUAUUAUCACAAUUACUGUGCCCCCUGCACUUCCUGCUGCAAUGACUGCUGGUAUUGUGUAUGCUCAGAGAAGACUGAAAAAAAUCGGUAUUUUCUGUAUCAGUCCUCAAAGAAUAAAUAUUUGUGGACAGCUCAAUCUUGUUUGCUUUGACAAGACUGGAACUCUAACUGAAGAUGGUUUAGAUCUUUGGGGGAUUCAACGAGUGGAAAAUGCACGAUUUCUUUCACCAGAAGAAAAUGUGUGCAAUGAGAUGUUGGUAAAAUCCCAGUUUGUUGCUUGUAUGGCUACUUGUCAUUCACUUACAAAAAUUGAAGGAGUGCUCUCUGGUGAUCCACUUGAUCUGAAAAUGUUUGAGGCUAUUGGAUGGAUUCUGGAAGAAGCAACUGAAGAAGAAACAGCACUUCAUAAUCGAAUUAUGCCCACAGUGGUUCGUCCUCCCAAACAACUGCUUCCUGAAUCUACCCCUGCAGGAAACCAAGAAAUGGAGCUGUUUGAACUUCCAGCUACUUAUGAGAUAGGAAUUGUUCGCCAGUUCCCAUUUUCUUCUGCUUUGCAACGUAUGAGUGUGGUUGCCAGGGUGCUGGGGGAUAGGAAAAUGGACGCCUACAUGAAAGGAGCGCCCGAGGCCAUUGCCGGUCUCUGUAAACCUGAAACAGUUCCUGUCGAUUUUCAAAACGUUUUGGAAGACUUCACUAAACAGGGCUUCCGUGUGAUUGCUCUUGCACACAGAAAAUUGGAGUCAAAACUGACAUGGCAUAAAGUACAGAAUAUUAGCAGAGAUGCAAUUGAGAACAACAUGGAUUUUAUGGGAUUAAUUAUAAUGCAGAACAAAUUAAAGCAAGAAACCCCUGCAGUACUUGAAGAUUUGCAUAAAGCCAACAUUCGCACCGUCAUGGUCACAGGUGACAGUAUGUUGACUGCUGUCUCUGUGGCCAGAGAUUGUGGAAUGAUUCUACCUCAGGAUAAAGUGAUUAUUGCUGAAGCAUUACCUCCAAAGGAUGGGAAAGUUGCCAAAAUAAAUUGGCAUUAUGCAGACUCCCUCACGCAGUGCAGUCAUCCAUCAGCAAUUGACCCAGAGGCUAUUCCGGUUAAAUUGGUCCAUGAUAGCUUAGAGGAUCUUCAAAUGACUCGUUAUCAUUUUGCAAUGAAUGGAAAAUCAUUCUCAGUGAUACUGGAGCAUUUUCAAGACCUUGUUCCUAAGUUGAUGUUGCAUGGCACCGUGUUUGCCCGUAUGGCACCUGAUCAGAAGACACAGUUGAUAGAAGCAUUGCAAAAUGUUGAUUAUUUUGUUGGGAUGUGUGGUGAUGGCGCAAAUGAUUGUGGUGCUUUGAAGAGGGCACACGGAGGCAUUUCCUUAUCGGAGCUCGAAGCUUCAGUGGCAUCUCCCUUUACCUCUAAGACUCCUAGUAUUUCCUGUGUGCCAAACCUUAUCAGGGAAGGCCGUGCUGCUUUAAUAACUUCCUUCUGUGUGUUUAAAUUCAUGGCAUUGUACAGCAUUAUCCAGUACUUCAGUGUUACUCUGCUGUAUUCUAUCUUAAGUAACCUAGGAGACUUCCAGUUUCUCUUCAUUGAUCUGGCAAUCAUUUUGGUAGUGGUAUUUACAAUGAGUUUAAAUCCUGCCUGGAAAGAACUUGUGGCACAAAGACCACCUUCGGGUCUUAUAUCUGGGGCCCUUCUCUUCUCCGUUUUGUCUCAGAUUAUCAUCUGCAUUGGAUUUCAAUCUUUGGGUUUUUUUUGGGUCAAACAGCAACCUUGGUAUGAAGUGUGGCAUCCAAAAUCAGAUGCUUGUAAUACAACAGGAAGCGGGUUUUGGAAUUCUUCACACGUAGACAAUGAAACCGAACUUGAUGAACAUAAUAUACAAAAUUAUGAAAAUACCACAGUGUUUUUUAUUUCCAGUUUUCAGUACCUCAUAGUGGCAAUUGCCUUUUCAAAAGGAAAACCCUUCAGGCAACCUUGCUACAAAAAUUAUUUUUUUGUUUUUUCUGUGAUUUUUUUAUAUAUUUUUAUAUUAUUCAUCAUGUUGUAUCCAGUUGCCUCUGUUGACCAGGUUCUUCAGAUAGUGUGUGUACCAUAUCAGUGGCGUGUAACUAUGCUCAUCAUUGUUCUUGUCAAUGCCUUUGUGUCUAUCACAGUGGAGAACUUCUUCCUUGACAUGGUCCUUUGGAAAGUUGUGUUCAACCGAGACAAACAAGGAGAGUAUCGGUUCAGCACCACACAGCCACCGCAGGAGUCAGUGGAUCGGUGGGGAAAAUGCUGCUUACCCUGGGCCCUGGGCUGUAGAAAGAAGACACCAAAGGCAAAGUACAUGUAUCUGGCGCAGGAGCUCUUGGUUGAUCCAGAAUGGCCACCAAAACCUCAGACAACCACAGAAGCUAAAGCUUUAGUUAAGGAGAAUGGAUCAUGUCAAAUCAUCACCAUAACAUAGCAGUGAAUCAGUCUCAGUGGUAUUGCUGAUAGCAGUAUUCAGGAAUAUGUGAUUUUAGGAGUUUCUGAUCCUGUGUGUCAGAAUGGCACUAGUUCAGUUUAUGUCCCUUCUGAUAUAGUAGCUUAUUUGACAGCUUUGCUCUUCCUUAAAAUAAAAACAGAAAAAUAUAUCGUCCUAACAGUUAAAUUAACAAUCAAUCCAUAAAGUCCUAUAUCUUCAUUCAGCAACCCAAAUAUUACAUACAUUUCCAGAAUUUUCUUGAUUGUUACUUUCAGUGAUAUUCUUUAUAUUGGGUACAGGAGAAGUUUGGUGUUUGGUAGGUUUUUCAACAUUAGUUUUUGAGACUAGUUUACCUCUUCACAUUUAUGCUCACAACCCUCUUGUUAGAAAAGUCUGUGUUUAUAUACAGGCUGUAAGUUUGUGAUUGAUAAAAAGAAGAUGAGUGUUAAUUAGCCUCCAGUGAAAAUAUACUGAAAGCCUGUUUUCAUUUGAUUCCAAUGUUUCUUCCAAAGAAUUCUGUAUAAACAUAUGCCAAUUCCCUAUGAUGGUCUAGAGUUAGGAAUGAGUGUUUAUGGUGUUGCUUAUAGAACAACUCAGGUAAUCUCCAUUUCUGGUUUUAUAUUUUCUGUACAAACUGCCUGGGUUUUAUUUUUCUAAUCAGCAAGGUGCUUCACUGCCUUCUUGAGACGCCUCUCAAAGCUCUUAAAUGGCUCCUGUGCUAUGUGUGGUGUUGGCAGUCUAAUUUGCUUCUGUUAAAUGUUGUAGAACCUUUUUCACUAGGAAAUAAGAUUCAUUUCUUUCGGCAGUAGAUGUAGAUUCAUCUUUUAACGUUUCUUCAAAUUUGUUUCUGUCAGGCUUUGUGUUAUUUUAAAUGGUUUUUUAAAAUUUUCUUCUAUGUUUUCAAUUACCUAAAGACAUAGGAUAAUAGUUUUUUUUAAGUUAGAAUUUUACCUCAUAAAAUUUUUUGAGGUUUGAUGUAUGUCUCUGUCUUAUCAAUAAUGAGGCUUAAAAAAUACUGGAUUUGAAUGGCUGCCGUUUUUUCAAAGCAAUAUGAAUUUGAUGAGUUUGUUUUAUGCCAUUAGGUGGCGCCAGAGGUCAGAACAUGUCUAUUUUGAAUUGGAUCGUUACAAAUGAGCAUAUUUGAUGCGGAAAUUUCUGGGAGAAAAAAAAUUGAGGAAAUAAAGUUAAAAAAUUGACAUUCAUUGAGCCAAAAGAGAUGUGGAGAAACAUUUUUCACCUUUCUGUUUGGCCUGAUUAACAUUUAAAUUCUUGCCAAAAUUAAGGUAACUUUUAAAAAACACCUUUUAUAGGUGGAUCCAGCAGUCUGGCAACGCCCACAGUUACCACAACACAGAAAACUGAUCGUGCUAUAAAAUGGACGCUAAACUAUGAAAACAGUGUGACAUUGUUCUCUGUUCUUCCAGAGCCAGUAACAUGCUUGCUCGUGCUUUCUACUUCUAGCUGAUCAUUCUUUUCCCAACAUAUAUUUACAAAUUUACCAAAUUUUACCUAGAAUUUUAGGACCAAAUGGUUCUCACUCUUUAUGCUGCAAAGACCUGGAUGAUGUUUGGUAACUAUAGAAAAAUAGAAAUUACACUCAGGAUCACUGUUACUGCUAUUGCCACUGAUGAUUCCUGCAAAAAUAUAAUCGAAGUUUUCCAUCAAAUGUAUAAUAUGCUAUUAAUACACAUUAGAUGAUAACAGUUGUUCCAUGAAUGAUUCUAUGAAGCUAUGCAUCUUAGACCUCUUGAGCUGUGAAUUAGCACUAUUUUCUAUAGUUACUUAUUCUCUGGAUCAUUUUAUAAUUUCCAUAUUAAUUUCAAAUAUGCUCGUGUUAUUCUUCAGUGAUUUCCACAAUUGUGCAUUUUAUUCUUUGGUUUAAGUACUGAAGCAUAUAAUGAAAGUAAUUGCUAAGUAGCAGCUUAAAAAUUCAAUUAUCCGAUUGUAUUUAACAUCUUUAAGAGCAUGAUCAUAAAGAGCUAUUUUUGACACCCCCCCCCCACUUUUUUAACAUUUAGAGUUAGUAAGGGUUUUAUAUCUCUUCUGUCCAUAUUGUUUUCAAAGGAAUGAGGUGUUUAGGUGGCUGGAAAAGCAUUUGUAGGAAGUUAGAUUUGAAUAUAGACAAGGUGGGUUAUUCACGUUGAGAAUGUUAUUUGAAGAAUGCCUGUGAAGCCAGGUGUGGGUUCUACUCAGUGCCAUAGAUAGACUGAGUCUUCUCUCGUAGGUUACCAUUACAUAGUAAUUUUGAUUCUGAAUUUCACAUUAAAUUAUUUGAGUUUAUACAGACCUAAAUUUUAAAAUCUGUACAUAUAUUAUUUUGAUGUAUUAAGAUGAAUAUUGCUGAUUUAAAUUUUAUUUAUGCACAUACUUAAAGGACAGAAAUGUCUGGGAAAGUAAUUGUUAAAUAAUGAUAUGUAACUUUUUAACUUUUUAAAUAAAUAACAAGAUUUUUAAUGUGUGUCUCCCUCAGGGUUGUUUAAAGUUUUUUUUCUCCCUCAAGUAUAAAUAGUGGUAACUAUAUGUUUUGUAUCUUCUAGCACCAACUGCUGUAAAGCAAUGCUGCAAAUAAUGCUUGAAUACAAGUGGCUAAGCCAACAACAGAAUAAAUACUUUUAUAGUAGUUUUAUAAUCCUGAAAUUCGAAAGCUUUCCCAAUUGCACUUGCAUCUAAACAAAACUGUUGCAGUUUUUACUCUAUUUAUUUUGUUCCCCAUGUUUAUGAAAGUCCUGCACAGUUUCAAAGGCAUGGUAAAUAAUAUAUCAAUGUUUAUGUAGUCUGUUACAGAAACAGCUAUAGAUAACAUUAUCCAGUGAAGAGCAAAAUUCAAGCUUUAGAAAAUAUUCAUGCAUGCAAUUUUGACAUAUCUAAAAAUAGGUUUUUGUAUAUUUAUGGUGGGAGGUGGUUGGGAACUUUUAACAAAAUGGGGUGUUAAUUUUUGUACAGUCUGUGGGCAUUUACACAUUUUUAAUGUAUUAAAAUUUGGUAAUUAUGUGUACAUUAAAUUAAUAAAAGUUACUUCUAGUUAUGAUUUGUGAAUUCCCUAAGACCUUGGAUUUUUUUAAGUAACUUUAUAUCAGAAAUGAUACUGCAUCUUUAUAUUUUUAAAAUUGUAUUGCUGCUCAAGAAUGGUACCCUCUUGUCAAAAAGGCAUACAUUCAUAAUUGUACAUUCAGCAUUGUAAAUAAUCUUAUGAAACCUUUUUUGAUUGAAGCUAUUCAAAAUAAAAAUUUUAAUGAAUGAAA